GCAGAUGACGCGCGGCUCGGGCUUCCGCCUUGGGGAGCCGGCGGCGGAGUCCGGGACGUGGAGACCCGGGGUCCCGGCAGCCGGGCGGCCCGCGGGCCCAGGGUGGGGAUGCACCGCCGCGGGGUGGGAGCUGGCGCCAUCGCCAAGAAGAAACUUGCAGAGGCCAAGUAUAAGGAGCGAGGGACGGUCUUGGCUGAGGACCAGCUAGCCCAGAUGUCAAAGCAGUUGGACAUGUUCAAGACCAACCUGGAGGAAUUUGCCAGCAAACACAAGCAGGAGAUCCGGAAGAAUCCUGAGUUCCGUGUGCAGUUCCAGGACAUGUGUGCAACCAUUGGCGUGGAUCCGCUGGCCUCAGGAGUUACCCUGGAAAAGGAUUUUGGUCUGAGAUGCUGGGCGUGGGGGACUUCUAUUACGAACUAGGUGUCCAAAUUAUCGAAGUGUGCCUGGCGCUGAAGCAUCGGAAUGGAGUCUACAGGCCUCUAAGGACUUGAGAGACAUCUUAGCUGUUUCAUGCAGUUGAAUCCAUGGCAAGUCUCCAUGGCCAAGGGUCUGAUAACUUUGGAGGAACUACAUCAACAGGUGUUGAAGGGAAGGGGCAAGUUCGCCCAGGAUGUCAGUCAAGAUGACCUGAUCAGAGCCAUCAAGAAACUAAAGGCACUUGGCACUGGCUUCGGCAUCAUCCCUGUGGGCGGCACUUACCUCAUUCAGUCUGUUCCAGCUGAGCUCAAUAUGGAUCACACCGUGGUGCUGCAGCUGGCAGAGAAGAAUGGCUACGUGACUGUCAGUGAGAUCAAAGCCAGUCUUAAAUGGGAGACCGAGCGAGCGCGGCAAGUGCUGGAACACCUGCUGAAGGAAGGGUUGGCGUGGCUGGACUUACAGGCCCCAGGGGAGGCCCACUACUGGCUGCCAGCUCUCUUCACUGACCUCUACUCCCAGGAGAUUACAGCUGAGGAGGCCAGAGAAGCCCUCCCCUGACUGCAUGUGGAAGGGCACACAGCAGCAGGCAGGGAGGAGGCGGAGGUGGCAAAUAAACCUGGGCAAUUUUGUUUAUACAAAAAAUAGAAAAAAAGUUCCAAGUUUUUCUUUCUUCCCUCAUUCUUUUAUUUUUGAAAAGUGCCUUCACGUUGCAUUUUUAUUGGAGGAAAACCUCGCUCGUUCAGUAAGCAUAAUCUGAUUAACACAGAGAACGGCAAGCACAUAUAAAAUGAUUUUUGUAGGUCAUCUGCAAGUUCAUGGAAGAGCUGGGCCUAGAAUGUGGGUUGUUUCCUGGCCUGUCUAGUCUUUGUAGCUGUGAGACAUAGAUUACAGCCUAUGCUAAUUCAAACCUUUUAAAUAAAAUGUUCCUUAUCUCAAACUAGCUGGUCCUAAUGGACCAGUAAAUAAUAUUCACUUUCAGUCUCUUCUGGCUUCCUCUGUAGAGGCUCUAGGUUAUGACAGAGUUAGCUGUGAGUAUGAAGGAAAUAGAAGUCAAUGUCCAAUCGUGGCUAAAUUGGAGGAAAGAAAACAAUGGAAUCUGAGGGGAAUCAAACAAUAGUUAGGGAAUGUUCUAUUUUCUUAAAUUCCCUACUAGCUUUCUCACCCUCCUGUAGUGAUUGCCAGGUCCCUCUAGCCUCAGUAGUGGGAAAGGGAGUCAUUUACUGAACACCUACCCUGUGCCAUUUUACAUACAGCUCACUUAAAUUUCACCAAGUAGGCAGCCUUCAACAUCACAGGUGAUUCAAUCAAAGUAAUUUGCCAGGGGCCGCCAGCUUCAGCCGAGCUAAAGCUGGUGCCUAGGCCUAUUAACCCGAGCCCAUGCCUUCAUGUAUCACUGCAUAGUACAGAAUGGCAGCACAUACUGUGUGUAGACAUUUUUCUACACACGUGGUCAGCCAAGAGUAAAAGCCUCUGCAUCAGAAAGCAAGAAUCUCCUAUAGCAAGUAGAAGUGGUGAUGAGGGAAGAGGCCAGAGUUGUUUAAGGCUCCCAAAGUCCUUAUGGUCUAAAGGCUAAGAUCCUAAAAGUGCUAGUUUAGUACUGGAAAUCUGAAAACUCAAUGGUUUUUCCAUACUGAGACCCUUCCUUUAGCAGGAUAUAGCCUGGGCCCAUCUCUUCCUCUGCCUAUCCUUGUAGGACAUGCUCACUCCAAGCUCUGGA